AUAUUCCCUCCCGCCGGCCGGCUCCGCGGCGCGCAGCCACCAUGAGCACCGCCGCCUUCCACAUCUCCAGCCUCCUGGAGAAGAUGACGUCCAGCGACAAGGACUUCAGGUUCAUGGCCACCAGCGACCUGAUGUCGGAGUUGCAGAAGGACUCCAUCCAGCUGGACGAGGACAGCGAGCGCAAGGUGGUGAAGAUGCUGCUCCGGCUCCUGGAGGACAAGAACGGUGAGGUGCAGAACCUGGCUGUCAAGUGCCUGGGUCCUCUGGUGGUCAAAGUGAAGGAGUACCAGGUGGAGACCAUUGUGGACACCCUGUGCACCAACAUGCGGUCAGACAAGGAGCAGCUGCGAGACAUUGCCGGCAUUGGCCUCAAGACCGUCCUCUCGGAGCUCCCUCCUGCAGCCACAGGCUCCGGGCUGGCCACCAACGUGUGCCGGAAGAUCACAGGCCAGCUCACCAGUGCCAUUGCCCAGCAGGAGGAUGUGGCUGUGCAGCUGGAAGCCCUGGACAUCCUCUCUGACAUGCUGAGCAGGCUGGGUGUCCCGCUGGGCGCCUUCCACGCCAGCCUCCUGCACUGUCUGCUGCCACAGCUGAGCAGCCCGCGCCUGGCGGUGCGCAAGCGGGCGGUCGGAGCGCUUGGCCACCUGGCGGCCGCCUGCAGCACCGACCUCUUCGUCGAGCUCGCUGACCACCUACUGGACCGGCUGCCCGGCCCGCGGGUGCCCACCAGCCCGACUGCCAUCCGCACCCUGAUCCAAUGUUUGGGCAGCGUCGGCCGCCAGGCCGGCCACCGCCUCGGGGCUCACCUGGACCGCCUGGUGCCCCUGGUGGAGGAUUUCUGCAACCUGGAUGAUGAUGAGCUCCGGGAGUCCUGCCUCCAGGCUUUUGAGGCCUUCUUGAGGAAGUGCCCCAAGGAAAUGGGUCCUCACGUGCCCAACGUGACCAGCCUCUGCCUCCAAUACAUAAAACACGACCCCAACUACAACUACGACAGUGAUGAGGAUGAGGAGCAGAUGGAGACAGAGGAUAGUGAAUUCAGUGAGCAAGAGAGUGAAGACGAGUACAGCGAUGACGAUGACAUGAGCUGGAAGGUGCGCCGGGCAGCUGCCAAGUGCAUCGCAGCCUUGAUCAGCUCGCGGCCUGACCUGCUGCCCGAUUUCCACUGCACCCUGGCACCUGUGCUCAUCCGCCGCUUCAAAGAACGCGAGGAGAACGUCAAGGCUGACGUCUUCACUGCUUACAUCGUGCUGCUGCGGCAAACACAGCCCCCGAAGGGAUGGCUGGAGGCCAUGGAGGAACCCACCCAGACCGGCAGCAACCUCCAUAUGCUACGUGGACAGGUGCCCCUUGUGGUCAAGGCCCUGCAGCGGCAGCUUAAAGAUCGGAGCGUCAGAGCCCGCCAGGGAUGCUUCAGCCUCCUCACCGAGCUGGCGGGUGUCCUCCCAGGCAGCCUGGCCGAGCAUAUGCCUGUGCUGGUAUCAGGCAUCAUCUUCUCGCUGGCCGACCGCUCCAGCUCCUCCACCAUCCGGAUGGAUGCCCUGGCCUUCUUGCAGGGGCUGCUGGGCACCGAACCAGCUGAGGCCUUCCACCCACACUUGCCUAUCCUCCUGCCACCUGUGAUGGCCUGUGUGGCUGACUCUUUCUACAAGAUUGCAGCCGAGGCCCUGGUGGUGCUGCAGGAGCUGGUGCGGGCCCUGUGGCCGCUGCACAGGCCUCGGAUGCUGGAUCCUGAGCCAUAUGUUGGAGAGAUGUCUGCUGUCACCCUGGCGCGACUUCGUGCCACUGACCUGGACCAGGAGGUGAAGGAGCGGGCCAUUUCCUGCAUGGGCCACCUUGUAGGCCACCUGGGUGACCGGCUUGGGGAUGACCUGGAGCCCACGUUACUGCUCCUCCUGGACCGCCUGCGGAAUGAGAUCACCCGGCUGCCCGCCAUCAAGGCGCUUACGCUGGUGGCCGUAUCCCCACUACAGCUUGACCUACAGCCCAUCCUGGCCGAGGCACUGCACAUUCUGGCCUCAUUCCUGCGGAAGAACCAGCGGGCUUUGCGACUGGCCACACUGGCAGCCCUGGACGCCCUGGCCCAGAGCCAGGGCCUCAGCCUCCCACCGUCUGCCGUGCAGGCCGUGCUGGCUGAGCUGCCUGCCCUGGUCAACGAGAGCGACAUGCAUGUGGCCCAGCUGGCUGUGGACUUCCUUGCCACAGUGACCCAGGCCCAGCCAGCCUCUUUGGUGGAGGUCAGUGGCCCUGUGCUCUCAGAGCUGCUGCGGCUGCUGCGUUCGCCCCUGUUGCCAGCCGGGGUUCUGGCAGCUGCUGAAGGCUUCCUGCAGGCCCUGGUAGGGACCCGUCCCCCGUGUGUGGACUAUGCCAAACUCAUCAGCCUGCUCACUGCGCCUGUUUAUGAGCAGGCUGUGGAUGGUGGGCCUGGCCUGCACAAGCAGGUGUUCCACUCAUUGGCCCGGUGUGUGGCAGCCCUCUCAGCUGCCUGUCCCCAAGAGGCGGCAAGCACAGCCAGUCGCCUGGUCUGCGAUGCCAGGUCGCCCCACUCCAGCACGGGGGUCAAGGUCCUGGCAUUCUUGUCGCUGGCUGAGGUGGGUCAGGUGGCUGGGCCAGGCCACCAGCGGGAGCUGAAGGCGGUGCUCCUGGAAGCUUUGGGGUCACCCAGUGAGGAUGUGAGGGCUGCAGCCUCGUAUGCACUGGGCCGUGUGGGUGCUGGCAGCCUGCCCGACUUCCUGCCCUUCCUGCUGGAGCAGAUCGAGGCUGAGCCCCGACGACAGUACCUGCUGCUGCACUCACUCAGGGAGGCCCUGGGGGCCGCCCAGCCUGACAGCCUGAAGCCCUACGCCGAGGACAUCUGGGCCUUGCUGUUCCAGCGCUGCGAGGGUGCUGAGGAGGGCACCCGGGGGGUGGUGGCCGAGUGCAUUGGGAAGCUGGUCCUUGUGAACCCUUCGUUCCUUCUGCCCCGCUUGCGGAAGCAGCUUGCUGCAGGUCGGCCACACACCCGGAGCACCGUCAUCACAGCGGUCAAGUUCCUUAUCUCGGACCAGCCCCAUCCCAUUGACCCCCUCCUGAAGAGCUUCAUCGGAGAGUUCAUGGAGAGCCUGCAGGACCCAGACCUGAACGUGCGCCGUGCGACUCUGGCUUUCUUCAACUCAGCUGUGCACAACAAGCCCUCGCUAGUCCGGGACCUGCUGGAUGACAUCCUGCCCCUCCUCUACCAGGAGACAAAGAUCCGGCGGGACCUCAUCCGAGAGGUGGAGAUGGGGCCCUUUAAACAUACAGUGGACGAUGGGCUGGACGUGCGGAAGGCGGCCUUUGAAUGCAUGUAUUCACUGCUUGAGAGCUGCCUGGGCCAGCUGGAUAUCUGUGAGUUCCUGAACCAUGUGGAGGACGGGCUGAAGGACCACUACGACAUCCGGGGCACUUUCAGCUGUGGAAUACUAGCAGCAUUGAGGAGCGAGCUGCAUCUCUUCGUGUUGUGACCUGAAAGAGCUCCAAGCCCCAAUGUUGAGUGGCAAGAGCUAGUUCCAGAAGUUAGGACCAUUUUCUUAACAGACAGAGUGAGUCUGGGGCUGGUGGAGACGUCGGUUUCUUCAAUUUAUAUCUUUCUAUAUCAUUUUUUUAAAUGUUAAAGUUUAUUCACAUAUAUGAUAGAAAUCAUUUAAUUGUGGCGAAAUAUUAAUAAUACAAGUUACUAUCUUCAGUAACUUACUAUCUGCAGGUGAAGUGUUUUUUUUUUUUUUUUUUUGAGACAGGGUCUUGCACUGUCACUCAGGCUGGAGUGCAGUGGCUUGAUCUCAGCUGACUGCAACCUCUGCCUCCCAGGUUCAAGCGAUUCUCCUGCCUCAGCCUCCCAAGUAGCUGGGACUACAGGUGCCCACCACCACACUCAGCUAAAUUUUUUUUGUAUUUUUAGUAGAGACGGGGUUUCACCAUAUUGGCCAGGCUGGUCUCGAACUCCUGACCUCAAGUAAUCUGCCUGCCCUGGCCUCCCAAAGUGCUGGGAUUACAGGUGUGAGCCACUGCGCCAGGCUCCAUCUUCACUAUUUUAAAGUGCACAGCACAGUGGCAGUAAGCACAUUCACAUUGCGGUGCAGCCGUCACCACUGUCCAUCUCAGAACUCUUUUCUCCUUCCCAAACUGAAAACUGCACCCAUUCAACACUCUAUGAAUUUGACUACUCUAGGUUUCUGCCCUUGUAAGUGGAAUCAUACAGUAUUUGUCCUUUUGUGACCAACUUGUUUCACUUAGUCUGAUGUCCUCAAGGUUCAUCCAUGUUGCAGCAUGUCAGAAUUUCCCAGUGUUGUAUGUACAGACCACCAGUUUGUUUACCCAUUCAUCCAUCGCUGGACAAAUAUUUGGGUGUUCCCAGCUUCUGGCUAUUAUGAGUAAUGCGACUGUGAACCUAGGUGUUCCGAUAUCCUUUGGAAUCCUGCCUUCAGUUCUCUUCACUUUACCCAGAAGUGAAAUUGCUGGAUCAUACGGCAAUUCUGUGUUUAAUGUCUUAAGGAACUGCUAUACUACAACUUUAUUUUUAAGUUUUUAUUUAUUUGUUUGAGAUGGAGUCUCACUUUAUGGCCCAGGCUGGAGUGCAUUGGUGCAAUCUUGGCUCACUGCAACCUCCGCCUCCCGGGUUCAAGUGAUUCUCCUGCCUCGGCCUCUUGAGUAGCUGGGAUUACAGAUGUGCACCACCACGCUCGGCUAAUUUUUAUAUGUUUUAGUAGAGACAGGGUUUCGCCAUGUUGGCUAGGCUGGUCUUGAACUCCUGACCUCAGGUGACCCACCCACCUCGGCCUCCCAAAGUGUUGGGAUUACAGGCAUGAGCCACCACGCCCGGCCCCAUAUUACAACUUUAAAAAAUAUGUACUGUAAGCGUGAGUCACUUUUUAUAAGGAAAAAUUAAUACAAAGUAAUCAAAAGUAACCCAUACUUGUUUUAAAAGAUUUACACAAGAUGAAAGCAAAUAAAGAAGCAAGUAAUAAUCACCCAAAA